GCAGAGCUGCAGAGGCACCGGACGAGAGAGGGCUCCGCGGGCCCAGCUGGCAGCCAGGCCGGAGACAAGUUGCAGUCCCGGGCUCUGGUGACGCCGUGGCCGCAGGUCAGAUUUGGGAGGGCUUUUCCCGGCCCGCGGGCCUGGGCGCUCCGGGGGAGGGAGCUCCAAGGGCAGGGUGGCGGGGGAGCCGCAGCUCCUCCACGUUAUGGAAGAAAGGGGAAUGCUAGCCCCCUGCGCCUCCGAUCUUAUCCUAAGGCUAAAACCGGUCCUGUUAGGGCCUGUCCUCUGCCCAAUCAAGGUUUUGAGAGACUGGGUUCUUUGGGACCUGGGAAUGUUGGGUGGCCUAGUUUGCCUGGGCCUGCGGGUUCUUCUCCUGGCACCAGCACAACAUACCAGGGAGGGAGCUUUGGGCUUUAGGAUCCAAGCUUUCCCCCUCAGCCCUCCCUUAGGACCAAGAUGGCCUUGACCCAUCUUCCUCCCACCUCAGGGCCACCAGGGUCACCACUCUAGGGCUUCAGGCUGGAAAAGCAGCCAUGUGGGGCAAGAACAGGCAGGCCUGUGUUCUCUCUCUGGUUCUGCCGCUGGCUCUGCCUGGGGCUUCACUGCCCUGUCCUGGGCAACCUUCCUGUCAAGGUUGUUGAGAAGUUACUGCCCCAUCGUUGUGUAAAUCAUUAAGGGCAACCCACCCACAAGGAGUGGUUAUUAAGCAUGUCCACCUUCCUCUUCAGGUCAUCCCCACACAGCCUGGUCUGAAAGCCCAUUUCAUGCCCUUAGGGGCUGAGUGGUACAUUAGCGUUGAGGCCCAGGAUCCUGAAGACAUGGUGGUGGCGGGGGAGGGGAAUGACAUCUUGGGAUCAGGGAAGGACCGCUGUGGCUACUUCCGUAUAUCCAGCUUUACAGCUUCAACCAUCCAGAGCCCAGCUCUUCAUGCACUAUUAAAGGCCAGCACCUGGACAGACUCUGUGAAAUGCAGCAGGUGAUACUGAGCUUUCCAGUUAUGGCAGGGCCUAGGUUUUUUCAUUUAAUAGGAGAUGGAGUAGGGAUGAGGUCACUCCCUGGGUUCUCUCCUCUAGACAACCCAUCCAGGAACCCUGAUGUUUGGCUGGGGAUGAGGCUUUCCCUGAGCUCCUUUCUUCCUCUAUCCUAACCCCAAUCUCCAGGUUGCCUUCAGGAGGUCUUCGCCGGCUUUAGGUACUCCUUACUCGCACUCAGGAGUCCCAGCCUGAGUCCUCUGCUGCCUCUGUUUCCCUGUUGACUCUGGGUGGAGAGAGAGAGAGCAGGAAGCUUGCACUAAAUACAUGAGCACCUGGUAGUGCAUCCCUUCUGGAUCCAACCAGAGGAGACAAGCUCCCGCCUACCCUCUCUAUAUCACAUUUGCCCAACACCUGUCACUUGCUUUGAAUUAAACCUCCUUCUCACAUUUGAUUCUGGCAACCAUGCUUAGAAGUAAACAGUUCAGGCAUAUUUGCUCCCAUAGCUGGAAGAGGAAAACAAGGAUCAGAUUGGAGAAGUGAUUUAUCUAAGAUCCCACAGUGGACUGGGAGCAGCACUGAGACCUCAGCCUAGUCUCCUGAUCCCCAAGCAGGGCCCUGCCUAAGGAACACACUCUGCAGAGUGCUGGGCCAAAGCAGGGUUUUCCAACUAAUCUUAGAAGGUAAAGUCCAUGAAGGUAUGUACCAGGGAUUUCUGUUUGUUUUGUUCGUCACUUAAUCUCCAGUGUCUAUGUCAGUGGCUGGUAUGUAGUGGUGCUCAUGAAGUAUUUGCCGAAUCAAUUAAAGAAUUUUCGGAAAGAGUGAGUCUCUUGAACUUUGCUACCUACUGUGACCUUGGCCCAGCCCCAGGCCUUGAUUCACAGAGGCCUGCAGAGUCUUUCACCUGAUUCUUCUGAGUAGCUGGGGCUCAUUCUUUGCCUGUCUUUUUCUAGGGUCUCCAUUUUGGGACAUUCUAAUCCCUGAGCCCCUAUUAUUUUCAUCAUGGGCUUCUGCCUGGCUCUAGCAUGGACACUUCUGGUUGGGGCAUGGACCCCUCUGGGAGCUCAGAACCCCAUUUCGUGGGAGGUGCAGCGAUUUGAUGGGUGGUACAACAACCUCAUGGAGCACAGAUGGGGCAGCAAAGGCUCCCGGCUGCAGCGCCUGGUCCCAGCCAGCUAUGCAGAUGGCGUGUACCAGCCCUUGGGAGAACCCCACCUGCCCAACCCCCGAGACCUUAGCAACACCAUCUCAAGGGGCCCUGCAGGGCUGGCCUCCCUGAGAAACCGCACAGUGUUGGGGGUCUUCUUUGGCUAUCACGUGCUUUCAGACCUGGUGAGCGUGGAAACUCCCGGCUGCCCCGCCGAGUUCCUCAACAUUCGCAUCCCGCCCGGAGACCCCAUGUUCGACCCCGACCAGCGCGGGGACGUGGUGCUGCCCUUCCAGAGAAGCCGCUGGGACCCCGAGACCGGACGGAGUCCCAGCAAUCCCCGGGACCCGGCCAACCAGGUGACGGGCUGGCUGGACGGCAGCGCCAUCUAUGGUUCCUCGCAUUCCUGGAGCGACGCGCUGCGGAGCUUCUCCAGGGGACAGCUGGCGUCGGGGCCCGACCCCGCUUUUCCCCGAGACUCGCAGAACCCCCUGCUCAUGUGGGCGGCGCCCGACCCCGCCACCGGGCAGAACGGGCCCCGGGGGCUGUACGCCUUCGGGGCAGAGAGAGGGAACCGGGAACCCUUCCUGCAGGCGCUGGGCCUGCUCUGGUUCCGCUACCACAACCUGUGGGCGCAGAGGCUGGCCCGCCAGCACCCAGACUGGGAGGACGAGGAGCUGUUCCAGCACGCACGCAAGAGGGUCAUCGCCACCUACCAGAACAUCGCUGUGUAUGAGUGGCUGCCCAGCUUCCUGCAGAAAACACUCCCGGAGUAUACAGGAUACCGGCCAUUUCUGGACCCCAGCAUCUCCUCAGAGUUCGUGGCGGCCUCUGAGCAGUUCCUGUCCACCAUGGUGCCCCCUGGCGUCUACAUGAGAAAUGCCAGCUGCCACUUCCAGGGGGUCAUCAAUCGGAACUCAAGUGUCUCCAGAGCUCUCCGGGUCUGCAACAGCUACUGGAGCCGUGAGCACCCAAGCCUACAAAGUGCUGAAGAUGUGGAUGCACUGCUGCUGGGCAUGGCCUCCCAGAUCGCAGAGCGAGAGGACCAUGUGUUGGUUGAAGAUGUGCGGGAUUUCUGGCCUGGGCCACUGAAGUUUUCCCGCACAGACCACCUGGCCAGCUGCCUGCAGCGGGGCCGGGAUCUGGGCCUGCCCUCUUACACCAAGGCCAGGGCAGCACUGGGCUUGUCUCCCAUUACCCGCUGGCAGGACAUCAACCCUGCACUCUCCCGGAGCAAUGACACUGUACUGGAGGCCACAGCUGCCCUGUACAACCAGGACUUAUCCUGGCUAGAGCUGCUCCCUGGGGGACUCCUGGAGAGCCACCGGGACCCUGGACCUCUGUUCAGCACCAUCGUCCUUGAACAAUUUGUGCGGCUACGGGAUGGUGACCGCUACUGGUUUGAGAACACCAGGAAUGGGCUGUUCUCCAAGAAGGAGAUUGAAGAAAUCCGAAAUACCACCCUGCAGGACGUGCUGGUCGCUGUUAUCAACAUUGACCCCAGUGCUCUGCAGCCCAAUGUCUUUGUCUGGCAUAAAGGAGACCCCUGUCCGCAGCCGAGACAGCUCAGCACUGAAGGCCUGCCAGCGUGUGCUCCCUCUGUUGUUCGUGACUAUUUUGAGGGCAGUGGAUUUGGCUUCGGGGUCACCAUCGGGACCCUCUGUUGCUUCCCUUUGGUGAGCCUGCUCAGUGCCUGGAUUGUUGCCCGGCUCCGGAUGAGAAAUUUCAAGAGGCUCCAGGGCCAGGACCGCCAGAGCAUCGUGUCUGAGAAGCUCGUGGGAGGCAUGGAAGCUUUGGAAUGGCAAGGCCACAAGGAGCCCUGCCGGCCCGUGCUUGUGUACCUGCAGCCCGGGCAGAUCCGUGUGGUAGAUGGCAGGCUCACCGUGCUCCGCACCAUCCAGCUGCAGCCUCCACAGAAGGUCAACUUCGUCCUGUCCAGCAACCGUGGACGCCGCACUCUGCUGCUCAAGAUCCCCAAGGAGUAUGACCUGGUGCUGCUGUUUAACUUGGAGGAAGAGCGGCAGGCGCUGGUGGAAAAUCUCCGGGGAGCUCUGAAGGAGAGCGGGUUGAGCAUCCAGGAGUGGGAGCUGCGGGAGCAGGAGCUGAUGAGAGCAGCUGUGACACGGGAGCAGCGGAGGCACCUCCUGGAGACCUUUUUCAGGCACCUUUUCUCCCAGGUGCUGGACAUCAACCAGGCCGACGCAGGGACCCUGCCCCUGGACUCCUCCCAGAAGGUGCGGGAGGCCCUGACCUGUGAGCUGAGCAGGGCCGAGUUUGCCGAGUCCCUGGGCCUCAAGCCCCAGGACAUGUUUGUGGAGUCCAUGUUCUCUCUGGCUGACAAGGAUGGCAAUGGCUACCUGUCCUUCCGAGAGUUCCUGGACAUCCUGGUGGUCUUCAUGAAAGGCUCUCCUGAGGAAAAGUCUCGCCUUAUGUUCCGCAUGUACGACUUUGAUGGGAAUGGCCUCAUUUCCAAGGAUGAGUUCAUCAGGAUGCUGAGAUCCUUCAUCGAGAUCUCCAACAACUGCCUGUCCAAGGCCCAGCUGGCUGAGGUGGUGGAGUCCAUGUUCCGGGAGUCGGGAUUCCAGGACAAGGAGGAACUGACAUGGGAAGAUUUUCACUUCAUGCUGCGGGACCACAAUAGCGAGCUCCGCUUCACGCAGCUCUGUGUCAAAGGGGUGGAGGUGCCUGAAGUCAUCAAGGACCUCUGCCGGCGAGCCUCCUACAUCAGCCAGGAUAUGAUCUGUCCCUCUCCCAGAGUGAGUGCCCGCUGUUCCCGCAGCGACAUUGAGACUGAGUUGACACCUCAGAGACUGCAGUGCCCCAUGGACACAGACCCUCCCCAGGAGAUUCGGCGGAGGUUUGGCAAGAAGGUAACGUCAUUCCAGCCCUUGCUGUUCACUGAGGCGCACCGAGAGAAGUUCCAACGCAGCUGUCUCCACCAGACGGUGCAACAGUUCAAGCGCUUCAUUGAGAACUACCGGCGCCACAUCGGCUGCGUGGCCGUGUUCUACGCCAUCGCUGGGGGGCUUUUCCUGGAGAGGGCCUACUACUACGCCUUUGCCGCACAUCACACGGGCAUCACAGACACCACCCGCGUGGGAAUCAUCCUGUCGCGGGGCACAGCAGCCAGCAUCUCUUUCAUGUUCUCCUACAUCUUGCUCACCAUGUGCCGCAACCUCAUCACCUUCCUGCGAGAAACCUUCCUCAACCGCUACGUGCCCUUCGACGCCGCCGUGGACUUCCAUCGCCUCAUUGCCUCCACCGCCAUCGUCCUCACAGUCUUACACAGUGUGGGCCAUGUGGUGAAUGUGUACCUGUUCUCCAUCAGCCCCCUCAGCGUCCUCUCUUGCCUCUUUCCUGGCCUCUUCCAUGAUGAUGGGUCUGAGCUCCCCCAGAAGUAUUACUGGUGGUUCUUCCAGACCGUACCAGGCCUCACGGGGGUUGUGCUGCUCCUGAUCCUGGCCAUCAUGUAUGUCUUUGCCUCCCACCACUUCCGCCGCCGCAGUUUCCGGGGCUUCUGGCUGACCCACCACCUCUACAUCCUGCUCUAUGUCCUGCUCAUCAUCCAUGGUAGCUUUGCCCUGAUCCAGCUGCCCCGUUUCCACAUCUUCUUCCUGGUCCCAGCAAUCAUCUAUGGGGGCGACAAGCUGGUGAGCCUGAGCCGGAAGAAGGUGGAGAUCAGCGUGGUGAAGGCGGAGCUGCUGCCCUCAGGAGUGACCCACCUGCGGUUCCAGCGGCCCCAGGGCUUUGAGUACAAGUCAGGGCAGUGGGUGCGGAUCGCUUGCCUGGCUCUGGGGACCACCGAGUACCACCCCUUCACACUGACCUCUGCGCCCCAUGAGGACACGCUUAGCCUGCACAUCCGGGCAGCAGGGCCCUGGACCACUCGCCUCAGGGAGAUCUACUCAGCCCCGACGGGUGACAGAUGUGCCAGAUACCCAAAGCUGUACCUUGAUGGACCAUUUGGAGAGGGCCACCAGGAGUGGCAUAAGUUUGAGGUGUCAGUGUUAGUGGGAGGGGGCAUUGGGGUCACCCCUUUUGCCUCCAUCCUCAAAGACCUGGUCUUCAAGUCAUCCGUCAGCUGCCAAGUGUUCUGUAAGAAGAUCUACUUCAUCUGGGUGACGCGGACCCAGCGUCAGUUUGAGUGGCUGGCUGACAUCAUCCGAGAGGUGGAGGAGAAUGACCACCAGGACCUGGUGUCUGUGCACAUCUACAUCACCCAGCUGGCUGAGAAGUUCGACCUCAGGACCACUAUGCUGUACAUCUGUGAGCGGCACUUCCAGAAGGUUCUGAACCGGAGUCUAUUCACAGGCCUGCGCUCCAUCACCCACUUUGGCCGUCCCCCCUUUGAGCCCUUCUUCAACUCCCUGCAGGAGGUCCACCCCCAGGUCCGGAAGAUCGGGGUGUUUAGCUGUGGCCCCCCUGGCAUGACCAAGAAUGUGGAAAAGGCCUGUCAGCUCAUCAACAGGCAGGACCGGACUCACUUCUCCCACCAUUAUGAGAACUUCUAGGCCCCUGCCCGGGGGUUCUGCCCACUGCCCAGUUGAGCAGAGGUUUGAGCCCACACCUCACCUCUGUUCUUCCUAUUUCUGGCUGCCUCAGCCUUCUCUGAUUUCCCACCUCCCAACCUUGUUCCAGGUGGCCAUAGUCAGUCACCAUGUGUGGGCUCAGGGACCCCCAGGACCAGGAUGUGUCUCAGCCUGGAGAAAUGGUGGGGGGGCAGUGUCUAGGGACUAGAGUGAGAAGUAGGGGAGCUACUGAUUUGGGGCAAAGUGAAACCUCUGCUUCCAGACUUCAGAAACAAAUCUCAGAAGACAAGCUGACCUGACAAGUACUAUGUGUGUGCAUGUCUGUAUGUGUGUUGGGGCGGUGAGUGUAAGGAUGCAGUGGGAGCAUGGAUGCUGGCAUCUUAGAACCCUCCCUACUCCCAUACCUCCUCCUCUUCUGGGCUCCCCACUGUCAGACGGGCUGGCAAAUGCCUUGCAGGAGGUAGAGGCUGGACCCAUGGCAAGCCAUUUACAGAAACCCACUCGGCACCCCAGUCUAACACCACAACUAAUUUCACCCAAGGUUUUAAGCACGUUCUUUCAUCAGACCCUGGCCCAAUACCUAUGUAUGCAAUGCUCCUCAGCCCUCUUCUCCCUGCUCCAGUAGUCUCCCUUCCAAAUAAAUCACUUUUCUGCC